GGUGUCAGUUCGAGGCGCCGCCGCCGCCGCCGCAGCCGCCGGAGCCGCAAUGCCUAAAGGAGGAAGAAAGGGAGGCCACAAAGGCCGGGCGAGGCAGUAUACAAGCCCUGAGGAGAUCGACGCGCAGCUGCAGGCUGAGAAGCAGAAGGCCAGGGAAGAAGAGGAGCAAAAAGAAGGUGGAGAUGGGGCUGCAGGUGACCCCAAAAAGGAGAAGAAAUCUCUAGACUCAGAUGAGAGUGAGGAUGAAGAAGAUGACUACCAGCAAAAGCGCAAAGGCGUUGAAGGGCUCAUCGACAUCGAGAACCCCAACCGGGUGGCACAGACAACCAAAAAGGUCACACAACUGGAUCUGGACGGGCCAAAGGAGCUUUCGAGGAGAGAACGAGAAGAGAUUGAGAAGCAGAAGGCAAAAGAGCGUUACAUGAAAAUGCACUUGGCCGGGAAGACAGAGCAAGCCAAGGCUGACCUGGCCCGGCUGGCCAUCAUCCGGAAACAGCGGGAGGAGGCUGCCCGGAAGAAGGAAGAGGAAAGGAAAGCAAAAGACGAUGCCACAUUGUCAGGAAAACGAAUGCAGUCACUCUCCCUGAAUAAGUAACUGCGACCCGUGGGAGGAGAUGCCGGGGACCUGGGCCGCGCUGCCAGGACCUCUGCUGUGUCUCGCCCACCCUGUGCCCUGGCGCCGCUGCAACAGCCCCUCAUGGCCAGGAGCCCCCCAUGGCCUGGGGCCUCCUCUUCAUCUUGGCACAGAAAUUGUUUGGGGGAUGGGGGGGGGGACUGGGGGAGGGGUAGCUGCUAUCUUUGAGACAGAAAGAUGCAGGACAGCAUUUCAUAUGUAACCAUUUGAAUGUUUUUGCUGUUUUUAGAAUUCAGAGCCCUUGCUGGGGGGUGCCUGGGAGAUGGGGUAAGAAGAGCUUUCAUUUGUCUGGUAGAUAGAUAGCAUGUAAGGGGGUGGUUGUCCCAGGAGGCAGCUGCUGACAGGUUUGCUACACACAGCCCCGGACUGUGUUGCCUGGGUGCUCAUUCAGAGAGGGGCUAUCAUCUGGGAGCCUGUGCCCCUGGGUCCUCGAGGGUCAUGGCUUGUCCCUGGUCAGUCCUGUCUGACUGACCUCAGGGCCUCACCUCUCUGCCCUUCCCUGCCCGGUUCCUACUCACCUGGCUAGGGCCAGUGCCCAUUUUCAGCCCUACCCAUUGAUCAUUUCAAGAAACCUCUGUUUACUGUGUGGCACCCAGGCAAAACAUGCUCCACAAAUUCAACUUGUAUAUUUGGCAGAUUAAACUUGACAUUAUCGUAAUCUUUGUUUUGGCAAUCCAUCCUUUGGCUUCCGUGCUCGAGCCGUUUUUACCCAGCUGGGUACGGUGCCACGUUCAGGCACGUGCACCCGGCAAGGUUCAGGGCACAUACCUACCUGGGGCAUGACAUCUGUCAGGUGGCACCGAGCAGGAUGCGGGGAUGGACCCUAGAUACCACAGCCUGCCCCCUCCCCUCCUUUAGCCAAGUCAGGAUCUUAGGCCUCAGCAGGCAGGGACCCUUCCAGGCCACAGUAGGCUGAAGCAGCACCAGGAUCCUGGCCUGGCCUGGCCUGUAGGUGUCCCCUGGUGGUUAUAAUUCUGUAACUCUAGGGGAGAAGGGGAAUAGCACUAGCAUUGGAUGUCGCCAAGGCCCACAUUUUCCUGAGAGAAGCCACAAAAGAUGUGCAAAUGCCCUUCAGCACAGGACCUGGUGACAUGACAUAAACUCCAAGACAGAACCUCAGUUUACAGCACACGAAAAAAAUAUCUUGCCAACAUUGUAAUGACAAAAUAAAUUCCCGUGAAGUUCCACAACCAGGCCGGGCAUGGUGGCUCAUGCCUGUAAUCCCAGCACUUUGGGAGGUGAGGUGGGUGGAUCAUCUGAGGUCAGGAGUUCAAGACCAGCCUGGCCAACAUGGAGAAACUCCGUCUCUACUAAAAAUACAAAAAUUAACCAGGCUUGGUGGUGUAUGCCUGUAAUCCCAGCUACUUGGGAGGCUGAGGCAGGAGAAUCGCUUGAUCCCAGGAAGGCAGAGGUGGCAGUGAGCUGAGAACGCACAACUGCACUCCAGCCUGGGUGACGAGCAAAACUCCAUCUCAAAACAAAAGUUCCACAACCAGCCUGGAGUGUGUAGCCCCUUUGUCCAGGAAUUUGACUAGUCAAUCAGUGACACCUGGUACUGGCAGUUUUGGGAGUGGCAGCCCAGGAUGGACAGCAGUGGGGAGGGAACCAUUUGGCAUAAGGCCGUUGGGCUUCAGGAUCAAUUUUGUUGGCAAGCAGUAAAAAUAAGCUAUCUACCUAUGGCCGUGCAAACACCAAUCUCUCCCUGGAGUCCCAGCUACUUGGGAGGCUGAGGCAGAAGGAUUGCUCCCACGAGUUCUAGUGCAGCCUGGAAAACUUAGCAAGACCCCAAGGAAAUAACAAAAAACCUCUCCUUCCACAUAGGCAAGCAUGUCCAUAAUUACUUUUUUUUUUUUUUUUUUUUUUACACAGUUGCAUUUUAUUACCUCCACAUUUUGAAGCAGUUCAUGACCAGCAUAGUGCUUUGGGGGCAUUUUUUUUUUUUUUCAAUAAAUGAAAGCAUUUAAGAAAAA